AGUUGCACGCUGAGCCGCGGACACCAUGCAGUCGGAUGAUGUUAUCUGGGAUACACUAGGAAACAAGCAAUUUUGUUCCUUCAAAAUAAGAACCAAGACUCAGAGCUUCUGCCGAAAUGAAUAUAGCCUGACUGGACUGUGUAAUCGGUCAUCCUGUCCCCUGGCAAAUAGUCAGUAUGCCACUAUUAAAGAAGAGAAAGGACAGUGCUACUUGUAUAUGAAGGUUAUAGAACGAGCGGCUUUUCCUCGGCGUCUCUGGGAACGGGUCCGGCUUAGUAAAAACUAUGAGAAAGCACUGGAGCAAAUAGAUGAAAAUCUGAUUUACUGGCCCCGUUUCAUUCGACACAAAUGUAAGCAGAGAUUCACCAAGAUCACCCAAUACCUAAUUCGAAUUAGAAAACUUACACUAAAGCGACAGAGGAAACUUGUUCCUUUGAGUAAGAAGGUGGAGCGUAGGGAGAAAAGAAGAGAGGAAAAGGCAUUAAUAGCUGCUCAGCUGGACAAUGCCAUUGAGAAGGAAUUACUGGAGAGACUGAAACAAGAUACGUAUGGCGACAUCUACAACUUCCCCAUUCAUGCCUUCGACAAAGCCCUGGAACAACAGGAGGCAGAGAGUGACUCUUCAGAUACUGAGGAAAAAGAUGAUGAUGAUGAUGAUGAGGAAGAUGUGGGGAAAAGAGAAUUUGUCGAAGAUGGUGAGGUAGAUGAGAGUGACAUAAGUGAUUUUGAGGAUAUGGAUAAACUGGAUGCCAGCAGUGAUGAAGAUCAGGAUGGUAAAUCCUCCAGUGAGGAGGAGGAAGAAAAGGCCCUUAGUGCGAAACACAAAGGCAAAAUGCCCUUGAGAGGACCACUGCAGAGAAAACGAGCCUAUGUGGAAAUAGAAUACGAGCAGGAGACAGAGCCCGUGGCCAAAGCCAAAACCACGUGAUUUCCCUUUCAGCAUUUAUACCCAGGACUGAACAUGCAGAACUGUUUUUUUUUUUUUUUUAUCUUAAACACAUACACACCUCCAGUUUUUGCUCUUUUGUGUUGUACUGAACACAAUAUUUGUGUUUUUAUUAUUUAUGCCACGUCAGUGGGGCAAGAAAUCUGGAGUGAGUGAAGAAAGCUAAGUUGUGAACAAGAGUGUUUUUAUAGCAUAUGUGUUGAAGUAACAGCUUGUGCCCGAGAAACUUAACAGAUGAGUUCUUGAAUCUGGGAUGAGAUGACGGAUGUAAAUAUUUCUAAAUUUUAAAUGCUACAUUACUUGGUGUCCUUUUUUCUCCCAAACUUUAUUUAGAAAUGGAAGGAGUUCAAUUUUUUCUUGUUCUACUUUCCCUAUUCUUAUGGAGGUAAAAGGAAAGGAAGGAAGGAAAAAGCAGCUUUCACUUACAAAGUUUCGUGUAAAAAUAUCUUUUUUUCUUAAAUAACUCCAUUCAUACAAAUUGGGAUGGGAAGAAAAUCCUUUCCUCUUGGGAAAGUAAUACAAGUCUUAAGUUCCAUUGUAGGGUGCGCCUUCAGAAACCUGCUGCACUUUUCUGAUAUAGUUCACCACUUUUCUGUCUUCACAGCUUUGGGGAAUUUUGGCCAGGAGACCCUGAAACAUGAAACCAAACAGGCUUUGAUAUUUUUUUUUUUUUAAUUACUUUCCCCUUUUGCUUGAUUCUUCUUCCUUGGUAUCAUAUUCAAAGGAGGAAAGAAUGGAUGACACUUAGGGACAGGUCACUAAGCAGAAUAGGUAUUAGUUGGUUUUUUAUUAUUUUUAAAUUUAUAUAGCUCUCAUGUAUUGAAGGUGCUACUUUAAAAACUGUGUUAAUGUACUUGCAAAUCUCCUGCUGGCUCAUGAAACAGCAGAAUUCCAGCCAAGGCAAAUUCAGUUGGAUCUAGGGCUUGAAAACUGCCCAAGAUUAAAGAGCUAAGAUGAAAUAGUUUGAAUAAACUGGUAAAAUAACAAUUCAUACUAUCUCUACAUAUUUUUAGGAUAUGAAUUUUUUUUUCCUGCUGGGUAGAUUGUCCAGUGACUUAUGGCAUGAAUUUCUUUUCAUGCUACCUUCAAUCUUCAACUAAAGAUUUCUAAAAGGGGUAAGAAAUGAGGCAGUAGUUUAUUAAAUACAUAGAAGUACACAGCUAUUAUAUGCUGUGGCUUUGAGAAGUUAACUUUUGUGGAAUAUGAAACCAAAGGAAGAAUUUCCAUGUAGAUAAAUUAAGAAUAGGGAAAAACAUCUACCUAAAAGAUGGUUGUCCCUAAAAAACUGGAAACAUCUGAAAUGCUCUAUUUAUGUUAUUAUUCCUGGGAGCUUAUAGCCCAUUAUUUUUACUUUUUUUUUUUAAUUCAGAAGACUAGAACAGAACUUAAAUUUUACAAACUUUUGAUCAUAAUGCUUUUGCCCAUACUGUCUCGUCCUUAGCCCCAGUGACAUGUGCUGAUCCUCCUGCCUUUAGUUCUAAAUGGUUCUGAAUAGCUUUAAAAGAUGAAUAAGAAAAAAGAUCAAGCUCUUUUGAGGCUAGAGGGCUCAUAUGGAGAUCUAAAACCCUCCAUGUUCAUUUCCAGACUUGGUCAGGCACAUACAUAGUAAAUUAUAAUCAAUCAUGGGAAUUACAUAAGGAUAAUGAGGCCCAACUGAAACCAAGUUUCAGUCUGCCUUACCUUUACCCGUCCUUGAGAACAGCGGUCCAGGAGAAUCAGGCAGUCUGUGGCCUCCUGUAGCAGGGCGCUCUUAACAGACUCAGGUGUAAGGUUUGGAUCCCUUGCUACAUCACAAAUCAGUUUCAAGAGGGCCUUCAGUAAGACCACAAGUCUGCAGGAAACUCUGGAAUCAGGAAGAAAAGCUAUGUUCAUACUCUAAAUCUGGAUAUUAAAAUUGGAAGAGACUUCAAAGACUGUCAAGUGGAAAGCUAUCAUUUCCUAAAUUAAGGAACUUAGGUCAAAGUUAAAUGAAAAAGACCUAAAAACAGAACCAAAGACAGCCUCUAGAUUUCUUACCCUCAAGUCUCCUGUUAGCAUACUGCCUAUACACACAGACACACCCUCUGCCACACUGCUCUCUUCCUUCCAGAAGCUUGGUUCUACUGUAAGCAACAGCUCCUUCAUGGGCUGAGAAGGGGAAACCAGGAUCUCCCCAACCAAGGGCCUAUACUUUUAUUUUUCAACUCUAUUAACUGAACUAUGCUUGGAGAGAGCCCUGAAUCCUUUAACUUUAAUGCCAUCUUAGGCCUGGAAGUUAGAGUGAGGGAAAUGAGCUUGGCUUCUGGGACUGUGUCAAGUUGAAUUUUCUGUCAUUUAAUUUCAGAUCCUAGCUCAUCAUCAGUGAAGUCCAGCCUACUUACUUGUAACUAUUAACCUUUCUAAAAGUUUUCAUCGCCUUGGUAAAGCUCCAGAAAUGGACAAUGCUAGUGACUGCACAAUAUUGUGACUGUACUUAAUGCCACUGAACUGUACACUUUAAAAUGGAAAAUUUAUAUGUAUUUUUACCACAAUAAACAAAAAACCCUAAAAAAACUUUAAUGAAAGGUGGAAAAUAAUUUAACUUACAAUGUGAAAAUACAAUGUGAAAUGUACAAUAAAUCAUAUUUAUGGACAGA